UGUGUACUUAAGGUCUGGUCCCAUAGCUUUCAUCAGAUGCUUAGAGAUCCAAGACCUGGCAUAUUUACAGUCAUGGCCCAAACUGAAGAUCCACAUAUACUUCAUCCACUUUAAUACCAAAUUUAUUGCGACCCUUCACUCAGUCUUACGUACUUGUACAUAGAACUCAGUCUACUUAUUUUUGUUCUAUUUAAGUGUUCUAACCUGUCAUCACUAUUAAAUAGUGGAAUUUGAAUUUUUUUUGUUUUUUAAACAAAUUUGUAGGGGGCAGAUUCUCUUUUCUUGGGUUUUUCUUUCAACUUAGUAAGGCCUUGGCAUAAUGAAUCGCACAUUUAUAGAUGUAAAAAUUACUUAACUAUGAAAGCAUGCAGUGGGGUCAAGUUCUCCAGCACAUAGCGGACUUGGAAAUUUAAGCCAAAAAGACAGUUUUGGUAAUUUGGCUACUCCAGUUACAUGUUUUAACUCCUUGAGGUUGUAUGGUUUAUUUCACAUUGGCAUGGUUUUGCAACAUUCUGCAAAUUAUGUUUAGUUUAUGAUAGUAUCCAAACACAUAAAAGUAGUGUAAAUGUUUUAACAUUUUUUGCUCAGUUAAUGUGAAUUUGGCAGGAAAUACUGCGAUAAUUUAGGACUGCUCCGUUUUCAGUCAAGAUCUGAAAUAAAAUGUUCAAUUCCUAAAUGGAAAUUUAAGAUGUUUGUUUUAAAGCUAGGAGUAAUAUUUUUUUUAUUUACAUGAACUACUCAGCUAAAAUCAUUACAUAUGAAAUAGAAGUAUUUUCUUCACAUUUUUUUUAUGUGCAGUAAGAUUAUACUGAAGAAACCCAUUUAAAAGUUUCAUUCUGGGAUCUACAGUUUAUAUACAGGAUAACUUCAAACUAAUGUGUACUAAUGCCAUGAUUUACAAUAAACCAGAGACCAUUUAUUAUAAAGCUGCAAAGAAGCUGUUGCACUCAGGAAUGAAAAUUCUUAGCCAGGAAAGAAUUCAGAGCCUGAAGCAGAGCAUAGACUUCAUGGCUGACUUGCAGAAAACUCGAAAGCAGAAAGAUGGAACAGACACCUCACAGAGUGGGGAGGACGGAGGCUGCUGGCAGAGAGAGAGAGAGGACUCUGGAGAUGCCGAAGCACACGCCUUCAAGAGUCCCAGCAAAGAAAAUAAAAAGAAAGACAAAGAUAUGCUUGAAGAUAAGUUUAAAAGCAAUAAUUUAGAGAGAGAGCAGGAGCAGCUUGACCGCAUCGUGAAGGAAUCUGGAGGAAAGCUGACCAGGCGGCUUGUGAACAGUCAGUGCGAAUUUGAAAGAAGAAAACCAGAUGGAACAACGACGUUGGGACUUCUCCAUCCUGUGGAUCCCAUUGUAGGAGAGCCAGGCUACUGCCCUGUGAGACUGGGAAUGACAACUGGAAGACUUCAGUCUGGAGUGAAUACUUUGCAGGGGUUCAAAGAGGAUAAAAGGAACAAAGUCACUCCAGUGUUAUAUUUGAAUUAUGGGCCCUACAGUUCUUAUGCACCGCAUUAUGACUCCACAUUUGCAAAUAUCAGCAAGGAUGAUUCUGAUUUAAUCUAUUCAACCUAUGGGGAAGACUCUGAUCUUCCAAGUGAUUUCAGCAUCCAUGAGUUUUUGGCCACGUGCCAAGAUUAUCCGUAUGUCAUGGCAGAUAGUUUACUGGAUGUUUUAACAAAAGGAGGGCAUUCCAGGACCCUACAAGAGAUGGAGAUGUCAUUGCCUGAAGAUGAAGGCCAUACUAGGACACUUGACACAGCAAAAGAAAUGGAGCAGAUUACAGAAGUAGAGCCACCAGGGCGUUUGGACUCCAGUACUCAAGACAGGCUCAUAGCGCUGAAAGCAGUAACAAAUUUUGGCGUUCCAGUUGAAGUUUUUGACUCUGAAGAAGCUGAAAUAUUCCAGAAGAAACUUGAUGAGACCACCAGAUUGCUCAGGGAACUCCAGGAAGCCCAGAAUGAACGUUUGAGCACCAGACCCCCUCCGAACAUGAUCUGUCUCUUGGGUCCCUCAUACAGAGAAAUGCAUCUUGCUGAACAAGUGACCAAUAAUCUUAAAGAACUUGCACAGCAAGUAACUCCAGGUGAUAUCGUAAGCACGUAUGGAGUUCGAAAAGCAAUGGGGAUUUCCAUUCCUUCCCCCGUCAUGGAAAACAACUUUGUGGAUUUGACAGAAGACACUGAAGAACCUAAAAAGACGGAUGUUGCUGAGUGUGGACCUGGUGGAAGUUGAGGCUGCCUGGUAUUUGAUUAUAUAUUAUGUACAUACUUUUUCAUUCUUAACUUAGAAAUGCUUUUCAGAAGAUAUUAAAUAUUUGUAAAUUGUGUUUUUAAUUAAACUUUGGAACAGCGAAUUUGGAUGUUCCAGAGGUUGGACUUGUAUUAGGUAAUAAAGCUGGACCUGGGACUCGUGAGGAAGGAAUGUGCUUGGGGCUGUUGCCAUACCUGUGCAGCAUUCUUUCAAAAUAGUGCCUUCCAAUGCUUCUUCCUUAUGUCCCACAGACAGGAUCAUCACUAAGAAGCGUUCUUAAAACGGCCCCAUCCAGUGAGAUUUUCCGUUAUACGAACAUACUUGAAAUAAUUUUAGAAUUUACUACUGUGGUUCUGCCCCUGCAUACCCAGUGGGAAUGAUGCCCUUGUAUGGGUAAUUAGGCACCUCCCACCCACCCCUGACAAAAGCACACUGGGAGUUUUAUAGCACUGUCACAUGGCUAGUGUUCUUUUUUGGUUUUUUCCGUUUUUUAAAGAAAGAGGAGUUACUUAGUACUAUAGCAAAGUAAUAAGCCAAAUAAGAUAAACUAAGUCAUCCUUGAAUAGAUCAGGGAAUUACCAGAUUACCAAAAGGUGACAUUUCUACUUUACUUACUGUUUAUCUGAAAUACAAAGGUCAAGUACCCAAGGAGUUGAACUCUAAGUAGGAGACCACAAGAUUCAUGGCCCCCUUUUAUCAGCAAGCUGAGAUAAAUGGUGAUUUUGCUGAAUCGGUAUAGAACCUGUUAUACACAAGGGAAAAAAAUCAGGAUGGAGAUAGAUAGAUAGAUAGCCUUGUUCAGUGAACAAAUUAAGUUUGAAGGCCCUUAUACAAUCCUUCUAUAAAUCACCCAGGCAGGAAGCCAUUUGAUUUCUAUUAUUUUCCUGACUUUGAAAAUUAAUUAGUAUUUAGGAAGAACAAAUAGGGUAAAGGAAAAUUAAUUCCCUCAAAAGACUUAAAAUCUUAUGCUAAAAGAGUCAAAUUUUCAAGUUGUUUGAGUCUACUUUUAAUCUCUAGUGAGUUCAUGAGGACCACGAAAAUAAAAUACCUUCAGAUAUUUGAGUUUUUCAAAUUGCUAAUUUAAUGUAUAAAAAGCAGCUAAACACUGGUACUUUAUAAAAAUGAAACAGCAUUUUGAAACAAAUGUUACAGAUCUAUAAAUAUUCAUUAUAUAGAAUAAACCCUAGUUACUUGCAUGCACCACCUCAAAUCAUAUUUCUUUACACUGACCUAUUAUAUACACAAAGUAUACAGUGGUUAAUGAUCUUCUCUUCUGUUUGUUUGUUUGUUUGUUUGUUAGGAAAUUUCCUCAAUAAGCCAGAAAACCUUAGGUAUUAUUUUCACAAAAGUUAACUCAGGAGAAAUUGUAAGGAAGUCCUUGACCCAUGGAGAAGGUCACUGUUUGUUUGUUUGUUAGAUACGUGUGUCUGUCAUAAAACAAAAUGACACCAGUAAUUACUUGGUAAUUUAAAAACAAGUUCAUAAAAAGAAAAUACCUGCAGGUAAUUUUUAUGGUCAGUUAUAUUCUAUAACCUGAACACUGAAAACUAAAAACUUUUACUUACAAACUAUUAUUAUCUGAGCACAGCACAGUGCUUUGCUUUAAUUGGAAAUAAAAAUGCAUGAGUGAGUGGUAGUCAGUUAUUUGUUAAACUCCCAACUGGGGUUUCUGUUGUUACUGAAGAAAAAAACAAAUAUUCCAAGAGUACAAAUAUGCUGACCUCAGAGAGGCCCAGUGCACUAAUGUGUUUCUAUGUUAUAUUAGCAACAGAAACCUUCCUGACUUGCCAGGAGAGCCCCCGCCGGGCAGCCCUGGUCACUGCUAGAUCUUGAGAGCACAGAUUUCAGUAUAGUAUUCAUGUGAAACCAGCCCUUCAUGUAAAAAGUUUUGGUGUGUAAAAAAGGCAACUUAAGCGAGGCUAAUUGCCCUUACCAGCAUUGUUGCCAUGAAAUUCCUUUAUACAGCAAGUUCUUCUAUUCAUACUGAUUCCACUUAUGUGCAGCACAUGAGAGCUGCCACUAGUCUACCCAGCACCUUUGUGCAAAUUAGAAUACACCUGCCCUUCCUCGGGCUGAUAAAGCCACACGACACAGCACAGGCAGACAGGUUCAAUUUUCGUUCCCUCCACCGCCACCCCCGCACUUAGCUGUACUCUUAAUUUGCAGCCCGGGGCAACUCAUCCCAGGACCCCAACAAGUCUGGUCAGUCACCCAAUCUGCAACCCUGUAUAAUCAUCUUGUAAAGGCUCCUGUAUGCAAGACUUUGUGUAGAACUUUACGGGGUUCAUGGGGACACCUAGCUAAGAAUCCCUGCUAUGUAGGGAAACUGAGUGCAUUAGAAAUCCUGGCGAUGCUCUGGUGAUGAGGCCACCGGUUAAGUCUUCCGGUUAUGAAGUCCAUUCAGAAAAAGUCACGGGCAGUUUGGUCAUUUCUCACCCUGUUGUUACAGUUAGGUUGACUUUCAAUUCCUUGGGAAGUUGAAGCACAGUAAGACACAUCCCCAAAACCUGGCUUUUUGCAUUUGCCUUGACUCACGCAGUUUCAGAGCAAGAACGGCUCAGCAUUUGUGAGGGGGCGGGCUUCCCAGAUCCAGGAGCCUCUGCAUGCACCCAUGCGGAGUAGAUCCUUCUAGUUUUGAAGCUCUCCAGAGUUAGCUGUGAAGACUAAAGGAAAGAAGAGAUGCACUCACAGGUUGUCCAAGUUGUCUCUAAACAGACUCCAUUCCUUUCUGGUAAGAAAAGUAAGAUACAGUUGAAGGACGGCAGGGGAGAACGCAAAGAUGUGUGAGUAAUCAAGGAAGAGGUGAAAGGCCGCACCUUACUUUCAAAGCACCUCUCUCCAGAAUGCUUGCCUCACAAGCUGCCUCAUUCAAAGGCAAGGCUCUGCUGCUCCCCGCCUUCUUGCUGUGACCACAUUCCUCAGGACUCUAUCCCCACAGCCAGCUGACCCCAUAAGCUGAUGCUAGACAGUAGUCCUCCUUACAUGUCAGUGGUUAAAAAGGCAGAGCAUACACUGGAGGGAAGAGAUUUAUGUCUAGUGUCUGAAAAGUCAUUCAAAAGGAUAAAAACCCCAUUAAUGUAUUCAUUUAAAACAAACAUGCCAGACAAGGCAAAAAGUAACAGUGUUAAUUGUGGUGUUUUUCUCUCUACCUGUUUGAAACCGUUUACAGAUGUAAAACACCCCUUUCAGCUUCAUUUACCAGAAUGCCUCUGUGAGAAAUGCUGUCAUUGCCAGGC